AGAAUAUCUCCCAGGAACUGCCCCCUUUGCAUCGCCGCACCGGGGUGGCGGCGCGGGCUGGGGGCCGCUGCAGCAGGUCUCAGUCCCUCCCUGCUGCCACGCGAGGAGUGGGGAGCGGCAGGGCCUAGGCGUCCCGAGUGGAGGAUGAGCCGGAGACGCCUGCGGGUCCGGAGCUGCACCGCGCCCGUGCGGCCCGCGCCGCCCGCCUCCCGCGCUCUCCCUUUGGCAGCAGCCGGACGCCUGGCGCGUGCAGGACCUGGGGCCGCGGCGCUCGCGCGGGGACGCGGGAGCCCAGGGUCGGCGCUGCAGGCAGCGGGGCGGCGCCAGCAAGGCCAGCUCCCCGGGGACCCUGGGGCAGCCUCGCGCCCUGCCUGCCUCCCUGGACUGAGACGCCGCGGGGCCUGGGCAGCGCUCUGCCGGCAGCUGGUGCUGGAACACAGCCGGGGCUGAGCUGCUCCCGGGGACCCUGCCCCUUCCAGGUGACCCCAGGAGAAGCAGCCCCGGGCCGGGGGGCAAGUUCCAGCCACCCUUCCGGGUCAAGAAGCCACGACUCCUGGUUAGGGGGAAACUUAGAUUUUUCUUUUGCAUGGAACUGCUGCUGUGCAAGAUUUGCCAAGGCUUAUAGGGUUUCAUUUUUUACUUGACUGGUGUUUGAGAAAAACUGCAAGGAAAGGGUGGCGAAAGGAAGAAACACUAUAAACUUUGGGGGCGGGGACAUUUUCUUGGAAGUGACAAGUAGCCUCAGAUCUGCAGUUCCUGGGCCAGCGACGGCAUCCUUUGCUCUGACACUCCAAGGGUCUGGACGCUGCCACAUGACCAACACCAAAGACCCCAAAAGAGCCAUGGAAUCCACGCUGGCGACAUCCAAUUCUGCCACAGGCCCCGUCACCUUCUCCCACGUCUUUGGUCAGCAGUGCCAACUUAUGCAAGCAGCUGUGCAAUCAUUGCACACCCUCAAUGACCAGAUUUCCCAUUUUAUUGUCACCAAGUCGAAGGCACUGGAGGAGGACAAAGACCCUUUUCUACCCACUGAGAAGGAGACUCUGAAGAGUUCCAUGAUAUUGAUGAGGCACCUCUUAAUGGAUGCUCAGGCCAAAAUCCUGAGCAUGAUGGAAGACAAUAAGCAGCUCGCGCUCCGCAUCGAUGGGGCGGUCCAGUCGGCCAGCCAGGAGGUGACCAACCUGCGAGCCGAACUCACGGCCACCAACCGGAGACUGGCGGAACUGAGCGGCGGCGGCGGCCCCGGCCCGGGCCCGGGAGCCGCGGCCAGCGCCUCGGCGGCGGGGGACUCGGCGGCGACGAACAUGGAGAACCCCCAGCUUGGAGCGCAAGUGCUCCUGCGGGAAGAAGUGUCGCGGCUCCAGGAGGAAGUUCACCUUCUCCGGCAGAUGAAGGAGAUGUUGGCGAAGGACCUGGAGGAGUCGCAGGGCGGCAAGUCCUCUGAGGUCCUCUCGGCCACCGAGCUCAGGGUCCAGCUGGCCCAGAAGGAGCAGGAGCUAGCCAGAGCCAAAGAAGCCUUGCAGGCCAUGAAAGCUGAUCGGAAGCGCUUAAAGGGCGAGAAGACAGACCUGGUGAGCCAGAUGCAGCAGCUGUAUGCCACACUGGAGAGCCGCGAGGAGCAGCUCCGAGACUUCAUCCGCAACUAUGAGCAGCACCGCAAGGAGAGCGAGGAUGCGGUCAAAGCGCUGGCCAAGGAGAAGGACCUGCUGGAGCGUGAGAAGUGGGAGCUGCGGCGCCAAGCCAAGGAGGCCACAGACCACGCCACGGCACUGCGCUCCCAGCUGGACCUCAAGGACAACCGGAUGAAGGAGCUGGAGGCCGAGCUGGCCAUGGCCAAACAGUCCUUAGCUACGCUGACCAAGGACGUCCCCAAGCGGCAUUCCCUCGCCAUGCCGGGCGAGACGGUGCUCAAUGGCAACCAGGAGUGGGUGGUGCAGGCGGACCUCCCGCUGACCGCAGCCAUCCGGCAGAGUCAACAGACUCUCUACCACUCACACCCCCCUCACCCUGCGGACCGGCAAGCGGUCAGGGUGAGCCCCUGCCACUCCCGGCAGCCCUCUGUCAUCUCCGACGCAUCUGCCGCCGAAGGCGACCGGUCGUCCACACCGAGCGACAUCAACUCCCCUCGACACCGGACACACUCCCUCUGCAACGGCGACAGUCCCGGCCCAGUUCAGAAGAACCUGCACAACCCUAUUGUACAGUCACUAGAGGAUCUUGAAGACCAAAAACGGAAAAAGAAGAAAGAGAAGAUGGGAUUCGGCUCCAUCUCCCGCGUCUUCGCCAGAGGGAAGCAGCGGAAGUCCCUCGACCCCGGCCUCUUUGAUGACUCGGACAGCCAGUGCAGCCCCACGCGGCAGAGCCUCAGCCUGUCGGAAGGCGAGGAGCAGAUGGACCGGCUGCAGCAGGUGGAGCUGGUGAGGACCACCCCUAUGUCCCACUGGAAGGCGGGCACCGUCCAGGCCUGGCUGGAGGUGGUGAUGGCCAUGCCUAUGUACGUCAAGGCCUGCACGGAGAACGUGAAGAGCGGGAAGGUGCUGCUGAGCCUGAGUGACGAGGACCUGCAGCUGGGCCUUGGGGUGUGCAGCUCCCUGCACCGGCGCAAGCUGCGCCUGGCCAUCGAGGACUACCGUGAUGCCGAGGCAGGCCGCAGCCUGUCCAAAGCUGCCGAGCUGGACCAUCACUGGGUGGCCAAGGCCUGGCUGAAUGACAUUGGCCUGUCCCAGUACUCCCAGGCCUUUCAGAACCACCUGGUUGAUGGGCGGAUGCUGAAUUCCCUGAUGAAGCGAGACCUGGAGAAGCACCUGAACGUGUCCAAGAAGUUCCACCAGGUCAGCAUCCUGCUGGGGAUCGAGCUGCUGUACCAAGUGAACUUCAGCAGGGAGGCCCUCCAGGAGCGCCGGGCCCGCUGCGAGACGCAGAACAUUGACCCCGUGGUGUGGACCAACCAGCGGGUGCUCAAGUGGGUUCGAGACAUCGACCUGAAGGAGUACGCAGACAACCUGACCAACAGCGGCGUCCAUGGUGCUGUGCUGGUGCUGGAGCCCACAUUCAAUGCCGAGGCCAUGGCCACUGCCCUGGGCAUCCCCAGUGGGAAGCACAUCCUCCGGAGACACCUGGCAGAGGAGAUGAGCGCCGUCUUCCACCCAGCCAACUCCACAGGCAUCCGGGAGGCUGAGCGUUUUGGAACGCCCCCUGGCAGGGCCUCCAGCGUCACGCGGGCAGGAAAGGAGGAGAACAGCAGCGGUCUCAAGUACAAGGCUGGCCGGGUAAGUCUCUCAAUGGAUUUACCUGUGAGUCCUGCAGACCCGGGAAAGGUCUUUUUUUCUCCUCCCGGGAGCUCUGUGGCUCCUGUGCUGGCCUGUGAAGGUGGAGUGCCAGGCCGGGUCACGGGGGCAUCCAGGACAGAUGCCCUGGAUGUACCUUCAAGGAACCUUCACGAUGCUUUGGGUACAGUGCACAAAGCCCCCGCAGGGCUUCGAGUAGCACCUGGAUCUCAAAGUGCAGGUCUCACCUGCCUGCAUGAGAAUCACCUGGGGCUAUUACUGAACUUGCAGAUUCUGGGACCCACCUUGGUCUCCUGGAAAAGGAGUUCUCUGGGGCGAGGGGGAUCCUGCAUUCAGCUAGGCUGCCCAGAGGGUUCCGGCGCAGCCCCAAACUCUGAGCCCCAAUCACUGAUUUCAAUUUGCGACUUCAGUGACCUGACCAAUAGCAAAGAUGAACCCUCUGGUGACUCCAACCAAACAGUAUGAAAACAUGUGCAGUUCAGGUCUGAUUGCACAGACUCCAACUGACACAGAUUCCUCAAUGGAAAUGCACAGACAGAGACGGCAGAACUGGGUAAUCCAAAAUGUCUUCCAUUUGAAGAAGGCAUGAUCCCCAUUCAUUCAUAAACAUGAAUACAUUGCCACUUUACCCUUAAGAAGCUCCAUUCUAGAACGUGCAUUCUAGUAAUUGGGGCUGAUAUUGCCCCCCAAAGGAGUGAAAAUUUGUUUUGGCGCUGGUGGGGGGUGGGGGCGGUGGCAAAAAUUCUUAUUCUUUCUAUGUAAAAGCACAAAUGUACAUAUGGUACGGAAGCAGAGGCGUAGUAUGUCUGUGGCAUUACAAUUUCACAGCAGGGGUGCAAUUAGGAAAAAACUGUCUAAAAAGUCUCCUUAGGGAGCAAUAAUAAUAAUAAAAAAAGAAGAUCUGGAAACACUGGUCUGGAAAGAAAGGCAGUCAAAUAAAUAGUUACAAAGCACUAAUGUGACUACUUUAACACAGAGAUGUGUGCAGUAAGAGAGAAGUAUUUUUGAAGGCCUACUAUGUGUGAUAAUAAUAGUCACUAUUCAUCAAGUACAUCAAGGACUUACUCGGUGCAAGCACUUGCUAUGUGCUUUGCAGAUGGGACUUGACUUUUUUUUUUUUGAGACAGGGUCUCUGUCAGGCUGGAGUGCAGUUGCACGAUCUCAGCUCACUGCAACCUCUGAUUCCUGGGUUCAAGUGAUUCUCAUGCCUCGGCCUCCUGAGUAGCAGGGACUACAGGAGCUCGCCACCACGCCCGGCUAAUUUUUGUAUUUUUAGGAGAGGCGGGGUUUCACCAUGUUGGCCAGACUGGUGGGACUUUACUUUUUACAACAAACCUGGGAGUUAGAAACUACUAUUCCCAUUUUGUAGCUGAGAAAAAUGGGCUCAGAGAGGGGAAGUGACUUGUCCAAGGUCACACAGCUGGGAAGUGGCAGAGCAGGGAUCUGAACCUGGGUCUGUGAGUCUCCAAAACUCGCAUUCUUUCUGCCACACCAGGCCGUCUAGAAUAUUCCUCCUUGACUUGGGAGUGCAGUCAGACCUCAUGGGCCUGCUCAGACAUUCUCACAGGUAGUCUCCAGGACACACUUCCUCAACUCUCCACCCACCAAGGAGGGAAGAAGGAGGCUUUUGUGAAUCAGGAAUAAUCAGACUAACGAUAUUUGUCCUCACCCUUGGUAACCAACUGAAUCCUUCCGGGGGCAGGGGGACACAAAGCUCUCCCCUAAUGGUCAUUCACAAACUCCCCUCAACCUCCCUGAGCAGGGAGUAUUAUUACUAAUAGGAGGAGCACACAGAGGUUAAGUAAGUUACUCAAUCACAGAGCAAUUAGAAUUGGAGACAUUUCCCAGACCUUCAUUCUUAAUUCUUGUUUCUCUUCUUCCUGUCCUUUGAUCAUAUUCUUCUCUUCUCAGCUGCCCCUGGGGAAGAUAGGAAGGGGCUUCAGCAGCAAAGAUCCCGAUUUCCAUGAUGACUAUGGCUCUCUUCAAAACGAAGAUUGCGGAGACGAUGACCCCCAGAGCAGGCUGGAACAGUGCCGUCUGGAAGGCUACAACAGCCUGGAGGUCACCAACGUGUAAGGAACUGGUGGCUCCACCAGACCCAACGUGAGAGACCCAGGAAGGAAGAGAAGCCAGAUGGCCCCAGGUGUCGUUCUCACUGUACAUAGCGGCCGCAGGCUGAGGAUGUCCCUUGCUCCUGGGCAAAAUCCCGAUGGACUCUGCGGUUUCAGCUCCACAGCGCCCAGGAGAGAGAAGACACCAGCCCACCUGUCUUGGGUGGGCCAUGGACUUUCCUGUUCAGCUGGAGAUGGGCCCAGAGGACCUGUCACAGUGUCCGGCCCUGCCUCCAUCCAGGAUACACAGGCUCCACCUCAGAGUGACCGUCACUGUGGAGCAGCCAAGCAGUCCCUGGAGCCUUAAACGGAGCUGCCAAGGUGGGAGGAGGCCCACAGUUCCCUAAAACACCCUUCCGGCGGGAGCAGGGGGGACCCCAACCCCACACCCCAGCGCCCAGUGCAUUGGCAGAGCCGGGUGCAGGAAGUGCUGCCUCUUGCCGAGACGUCGGACAGGGCGGGGGUUGGGGAACUCUCGGCUACAGCAUCUUACCCUUGACUGAGAACUUGGGUCCUGACUUGGCUCACUGAAUCUCUCUUGGGAGAAUGCAAAAUCCUUCCACCUGAAAAGCUCUGUGACACAUGGGGGUGGACGUAUUGAAGAGCUGUUUGCCGAUCCACCCAGGAGUGGCUACGCUGAGUGGGGAGCCGGUGAAUGAUCCGUGCAGGAGUGGGGCUUAGCAGCCACAUUUCUAGGAGAUGCAGAUAUCCUAUCACCAGAAUGAAAGCUAUUGGGACAACAGGAUCGGGGAUGACCGACGGCCCCAUAUGGUGAAUCUCUGGCCUGUGGUUUGGCUUUACUGAGAUUCCAAACCCCACUAUCUGCACUCCGUGACAGUGGUAUGGAGUGUGGCAAUGAGUUUGGGGUCUGGGGCAGGGAAAUGCUUGACAUUGUUAACCCAACAAACCUUUGUUGUGAUGUCCCUGUCACCUGAAACAUAGGUGACAUAGCUCACCAAUGUCCUAACCGAGACACAAACUCCACAGAGCAAAAUCAUUUGGUAUUGGUGGGGAGAACCCCAGCCCUUUUCUUGACCUGCCACUGUUAUGCUGUGUGGCUUCUUCCCAGUGGCCUCACCUCUCUGUGCCUCGAUGUCUUCAUCUACGAUACUUCUGGUUCCCUCCCAGGGACAUCGUGAGGAUUAACACUUGCUAAUAUCUGUAACACAAUUUGUAACCUCUCAGGAGACAAUGGGAAGUUAUGGGGUAGCUAAUUUCCCAUUUACAACACAGAAAUGAUAUAGAGCUAGUUCGCUCCAACUCUUUAGGUUGAAGCAGUGUGCAAAAGGAAGAAAAGAAAUGUUUAAUGUUCAGACCUGCCAAGAGCCUCCAACAGGGCUCAAGAAACAUAUAAAUCCCAUGAGCACAGCCUUGAAAACCAGUUUGACUCAAGCCUUCGGGCCUCAGUUCAUUGACCAGAUGACAGCCACGUGAUGAUUAGGGAAGGACGGAUGCAUUGCGAUUCUGCUUACACAUCGGGUUAUCAAAGCGAGUCACUUGUUGGAACCAUGAUGCUCGACCUCCUUCAAGGCCGUUUGCACUGGGGCUUGAGUUUCCAAGAUUCACAACAGGUGUCAGCCUCUGAGAACCCUCAAAGCGUGUGUUCUUCAACCUGGCAAAUUGUUUCCUCUCAUGGGGGAAGCCGAGCUCUGAUGAACUUGAGAAUUACACCUCUCUCAUGCCGAAGACCGUGGUGUUCCCCCUAAUGACAUAAACGCAGCCUUUCUUGCUGUCUGAGACCAAAUGUCUAGUUGGUAGACAGGUGGAUGUUUGGCCUCCUAAGGGCACACUUCUGAUCCUGGGCCCCAGGUGGUGAAUCUCUGGCAUGUGGCUUGGCUUUGUUGAGACUCCAAAUUCCAUUAUCUUCAUGACAUUCGGCCUCAUCCAUAGGGUCCUGAAGCUGCAGUCCACAGCUCAGAAAGGAGAGGUGAGACCUCCCUCCAACCUGGUGCCACAGGUCUCUCCCAAGCCACAUCCAGCCUGGAUGACCUGGGACCCCAGAAACUGCCGUUUGGGAGGCAGCAACAGCAACGUGCCCAGGCAGGCAGUUAUUCCCACAGAGUGAGCCAGAAUUGUAGCAGGGCACUUGAAUGCAGAGCUGAUGAUUUGAAACCAACGUUCACCCAACUUGUCAGAAAUGGCACUUACAUGGUUCGAUCUUGCUGGAGACAAGUGGACAAUUGGGGGUCACUGGCAGAGACAGUAUUGCCCAAAAUGUUCACAGCAGGAGGCCAGCAGGCCUGAGGCAACACGGGCAACCGCGAAUGCCUCUUUUGGUUUAAAUUAUGCCAUCACAACCCUCUUUCACCCAUGAGGCUCCCCAUCCCUGACAGCCAGGUGAGCAUUUGGAGCUGGUUUCUCAACAUGAGGAUGGGUUGGUUGUUAAAUUAACAACCUCCACAGUAUCAGAUUGAGUGAGCUUUGUCUGCUGGAAAAACCUGAAACGUCAACUCUGCUUCAAGGUCGGCAAGAAGAACAGAAGGCGGAGACUUGGCAGAGAGACUCAAGCUGAUUGUCACAGGCUACAGAGGGGCCAGCUCCAGAACAGUGACCAGCUACAUCCUGUCCAAGCAGCCCGAGUGUGGUCUUGGUCCCUGCAGGGCAAUGUGGGCAUCUGGACCUGGGGACGAUGUGGAUGCACUUCUUGGAAAGCUGUUGUAGCUUGUGCCUGUGGGUGGAGAAGGCACCUGCCUGGUAGACUCUCAGCUUUCUGACCCCCAGGAGCCUCUGCGAGGCCCCUUUGUCCUUGGCUGAGCCGGACCUUUCUUUUGGAAAUCUGUCUGUCUGUUGGCAUCGCUGUUUUCAGACCCCAGGCUGCAGAGGAGGGGAGAAGCCACACAACAAUCUGGACCCAAUAAAGUGGAGAGAAGGGCGUCUCUACACAGCCCGGCCAGCGUGGAGGGCCCCAGGACAGGGACCCAAAAGCUUGACGUCACUGAACAGGGCUGGGUACUGGCAGAACAGGAAGAUUUGGCCAGAGGUGACCUCAGUGUUCCCUCCAGGGGCAUCCAGGCCCCUCUGACCUGGGGAGAAGAAGGCCCAUGCUCAGGCCCACCUCCCUCUUCCCAUCAGAGCCCAUGCGUCCUGGGCACCACCACUUCCACUCUGCUUUUCGAGGCUCCGGAGGGCUCUUCCUGCUGUGAAAGGAAAGGAGAAGAAAGCCUGUGGGCAAUGGCAACCUCUGAGUCUGGCAUUCUUGCCAAUGGCUGGCCAGCGAGGAGAAUCUCCCGAGCCCUGACACACAAAGGCAUUUUGUGGCUGCAGAGGAAAUGGGUUGGCUCUGAACAAAGAUGCAGUUUCUAGGGCCGUGGCCCCAAAUCGCUUCCCCGAGAGUGAAUUUUAACACUGUAACAAUAAAUACUACUGCACAGCA